UUGAUUUUUUAUUUCUGAAAAUAUUUACUAAAUGGUUCUGUGGGCUAAGGUACAAAGCUACUAAUAUAACAAGAUGGAAAAUGAAUUCCUUAACACUACUAAUAUUAUAACAAUAAAGAUUUUUGUAGCAGUAAAUGAGUGGGUAUUACUGUCUUCCCCAGAAGCAAUCAAAAGAGUAUUUUAAAAGGAAGAAUCUUACAGUACUCCCAGACUGCUAACUUGGACAUCAUCUGAGAAGACAUCUGGUCCACCUACACCUGUCCUAAGAUUGGCGCAAGAUGUAGAAAACUUCCCACAGCAACUGUUAAAGGAACUGCAGCUGAGGAUUCUCAACCACCACAAGCAUCAGCAAUUAUUUCUGCCCACAUUAAGAAGAAAUGUGGACCUCAGACUGAGGGCUUUUCUGGGGACCAAGUACUACUCCACAGCUCCAGCUCUUGGUGGCAUGGACCUGGCUUACAAUCACCGUAUGCGGGACACAGCUCCUCUUCUGACUGCAGCGCACUCGGCCCGACGUGACCUCCACCCCUAGUGCCUGCGAUCUGACUGCCCGACAUGACCUCCACCCCUAGUGCCUGCGAUCUGACUCUGCCCGACGUGACCUCCACCCCUAGUGCCUGCGAUCUGACUCUGCCCGACGUGACCUCCACCCCUAGUGCCUGCGAUCUGACUCUGCCCGACGUGACCUCCACCCCUAGUGCCUGUGAUCUGACUCUGCCCGACGUGACCUCCACCCCUAGUGCCUGUGAUCUGACUCUGCCCGACGUGACCUCCACCCCUAGUGCCUGCGAUCUGACUCUGCCCGACGUGACCUCCACCCCUAGUGCCUGCGAUCUGACUCUGCCCGACAUGACCUCCACCCCUAGUGCCUGCGAUCUGACUGCCCGACGUGACCUCCACCCCUAGUGCCUGUGAUCUGACUCUGCCCGACGUGACCUCCACCCCUAGUGCCUGUGAUCUGACUCUGCCCGACGUGACCUCCACCCCUAGUGCCUGUGAUCUGACUCCGUCCUGGGUCUUAGGCUCUGGCUGCAGCCCUGCCCGCAGGCUCCAGGUCCUCUGCAAGGACCUAACUGCUGAGGACAAGCCCACAAGUGAGGAAACAGAUGCUCCUCUAGCUGACACUAAAGAUAAGAUGCCUCUAGAAAAACAAACUCCUGUUAUACAGGAACAGGAUGAUAAAUGCGAUAAGCUCCAUGUUUGUGGUAAUUUCCUACUUAGCAAUUUUCUCUUGCUGUGUCUUUUACAAACCAUAUAACAUAGAUAAACCUCUUAUUUCUUUCUUAGAGCCUUUAAUUUUGGUCAUUUUUCUCUGGGUCGAAUUUCCUCAAUAGUGGACAAAAGUCACCUUUUUUUCUUUUUUCUUUUUUUGAGACAGGGCCUUGCUCUGUUACCCAGGCUGGAGUGCAGCUUGUGCCAUCUUGGCUCAUUGCAGCCUCGACCUCCUGGGCUCAAGUGAUCCUCCCACUUCAGCCUCCCACGUAACUGGGACUAUACAGGUGUGCAUCAACACAAACCUGGCUAAUUUUUUAUUUUUUGUCGAGAUGAGGUCUCACUAUACUAAUUUAAGUAUCUGACCCAGGCUGGUCUCUCACUCCUGGACUUAAGUGAUCCUCCCACCUUGAACUCCCAAAGUGCUGGAAUUAGAGGUGUGAGCCACCUUGCCUGCCCACCUUUUUUUCUUUAAUUAAUAAGGUACUGCCUUCUGAAAAGGCCAGUGGUCCACAUACUAGUCCUAAACUAUUUUUAUUAGUUUCUUCAUUAAUUUACCAACAAAUAAUUACUAAGAUUAUUCUAUAAGGAAUAAGGAAAAUGAGAUUUGGGCAGAUGUUACAUUCUAGUCUUUCCUGUACUGCCUAAUUUUGCUGAUAUAAUUAAAAAGACUAAAAAAAUA